GGAGGGACCGGAGACCCCGCCCCCCAGAGUCUGGGGAAAUCGCCGUGUCCUGGGGAAGGGGUGGCGGCGGUGUACUGAGGGUGCCGAGACGUUGUGGUCUCUGUGUUUCCUGGUGGCCGGAGCCAGUAUCUCCGGGGACACGGAUGGCGCUCCCGGCUUCCUUUCCUUUCCAGCCACCGCCCUCCGCCCCCUCCUGGGGCCUGCAGAAAUGUAGUUAGUCCGUACCUCGUACCUCCUAACGCUUCCGCGCCAACUGUCCCCCCGGAACCGAGGGAGGAGUGGUCUAGGCCCCUUUAUUUUCCGCAGCUUUUUCUUACCCCUCCUCUCAGAUUGCUUAAGAUCAUCUCCGCGGGCUCCUUGCCCCGGCUAGCCCCAUCUCCUUACACCACCAAGCCCCCCUCAGCCCCCCAGCACACACCCAGAUACACUCACCCGUGAUCUUGUCACCUGUGAUGAUAGUAGUCCUUGGCGUCCAUUUGGCCAGAGGCUUUUCAGCUGCCACUGUGACAGACCCUGAGGUCCCCUCAAGCCAGUAGCUGCUGUCUCCACUUGCAACUUUCCUCUCCUCCCACUCCUAACAGCCAGUUUUGGCACCUCUUCUCAGCACCUGCGUUACUUUUAGCAGGAGUAUACCUACUUCUUGAGUGUCUUGAUUAAAAAUUUGUUUUUGUGCCAUGGAUAGGCUGUGUUCCUUCAGAAAGGUGUCAGUCUAAUUUUUGUUUUUCUGAACAAUGAAUGUUCUCAUCUUCUAGGCGCUUUGAUAACCCUGUCUGCCUUGGAAUCUGUACUGACCUCCCCAGAGGGAGACUCUUAGACCCAGCCUUUCUUGAACAACCUUGGUCCUGGGGAGCAGCGCUAGAUCCCAGGCUCUCAAUUAGAGGCUGGGCUUAGAACUGUUGCUUUUUCUCUAUCCACGCUCUGCAGGUGACACCCAGGGCAGCUACACUCAGAAGCCACAAGGAAUGCUAGUGGAGCCCCUCAUCCCUCCCAGCUUCUCUUCCAAGCUGCCCCGUGGGGCUUGAUCCAGGAAGCUACUUCAGAAAGCUAUACCCUUUUUGUACUCUGUGUAUAUACUAUAUUGCAGUAGACAAUCAUUCCAAGGGUACAACAAGGUUUACCACAAUGUGAGGGACUCAGCCAUUGCAAAUUGUACAGAUGAGGGCCCUUGGAAGAAAAUCCUCGCUGUGUCCAGGCUGAGGCGGGGGGCUAAUGACAGUGUGAGCUCUAGAUGGUGUGAGACCACCCCAAAGCCAAGAAAUGGCUACAGCCGUGGAACCAGAGGACCAGGAUCUUUGGGAAGAAGAGGGAAUUCUGAUGGUGAAACUGGAAGAUGAUUUCACCUGUCGGCCAGAGUCUGUCUUACAGAGGGAUGACCCGGUGCUGGAAACCUCCCACCAGAACUUCCGACGCUUCCGCUACCAGGAGGCAGCAAGCCCUAGAGAAGCUCUCAUCAGACUCCGAGAACUUUGUCACCAGUGGCUGAGACCAGAGAGGCGGACAAAGGAGCAGAUCCUAGAGCUGCUUGUGCUGGAACAAUUUCUUACCGUCCUACCUGGAGAACUACAGAGCUGGGUGCGGGGCCAACGGCCAGAAAGUGGCGAGGAGGCAGUGACGCUGGUGGAGGGUUUGCAGAAACAACCCAGGAGACCAAGGCGGUGGGUGACUGUCCAUGUUCACGGCCAGGAAGUCCUGUCAGAGGAGACGGUGCAUUUAGGAGUGGAGCCUGAGUCACCUAAUGAGCUGCAGGAUCCUGUGCAAAGCUCGACCCCCGAGCAGUCUCCUGAGGAAACCACACAGAGCCCAGAUCUGGGGGCACCGGCAGAGCAGCGUCCACACCAGGAAGAGGAGCUCCAGACCCUGCAGGAGAGCGAGGUCCCAGUGCCCGAGGACCCAGACCUUCCUGCAGAGAGGAGCUCUGGAGACUCAGAGAUGGUUGCUCUUCUUACUGCUCUGUCACAGGGACUGGUAACGUUCAAGGAUGUGGCCGUAUGCUUUUCCCAGGACCAGUGGAGUGAUCUGGACCCAACACAGAAAGAGUUCUAUGGAGAAUAUGUCUUGGAAGAAGACUGUGGAAUUGUUGUCUCUCUGUCAUUUCCAAUCCCCAGACCUGAUGAGAUCUCCCAGGUUAGAGAGGAAGAGCCUUGGGUCCCAGAUAUCCAAGAGCCUCAGGAGACUCAAGAGCCAGAAAUCCUGAGUUUUACCUACACAGGAGAUAGGAGUAAAGAUGAGGAAGAGUGUCUGGAGCAGGAAGAUCUGAGUUUGGAGGAUAUACACAGGCCUGUUUUGGGAGAACCAGAAAUUCACCAGACUCCAGAUUGGGAAAUAGUCUUUGAGGACAAUCCAGGUAGACUUAAUGAAAGAAGAUUUGGUACUAAUAUUUCUCAAGUGAAUAGUUUUGUGAACCUUCGGGAAACUACACCCGUCCACCCCCUGUUAGGGAGGCAUCAUGACUGUUCUGUGUGUGGAAAGAGCUUCACUUGUAACUCCCACCUUGUUAGACACCUGAGGACUCACACAGGAGAGAAACCCUAUAAAUGUAUGGAAUGUGGAAAAAGUUACACACGAAGCUCACAUCUUGCCAGGCACCAAAAGGUUCACAAGAUGAACGCGCCUUACAAAUAUCCCCUAAACCGGAAGAAUUUGGAAGAGACCUCCCCUGUGACACAGGCUGAGAGAACUCCAUCAGUGGAGAAACCCUAUAGAUGUGAUGAUUGCGGAAAGCACUUCCGCUGGACUUCAGACCUUGUCAGACAUCAGAGGACACAUACUGGAGAAAAACCCUUCUUUUGUACUAUUUGUGGCAAAAGCUUCAGCCAGAAAUCUGUGUUAACAACACACCAAAGAAUCCACCUGGGAGGCAAACCCUACUUGUGUGGAGAGUGUGGUGAGGACUUCAGUGAACACAGGCGGUACCUGGCGCACCGGAAGACGCACGCUGCUGAGGAACUCUACCUCUGCAGCGAGUGCGGGCGCUGCUUCACCCACAGCGCAGCGUUCGCCAAGCACUUGAGAGGACACGCCUCAGUGAGGCCCUGCCGAUGCAACGAAUGUGGGAAGAGCUUCAGUCGCAGGGACCACCUCGUCAGGCAUCAGAGAACACACACUGGGGAGAAACCAUUCACGUGCCCUACCUGUGGAAAAAGCUUCAGCAGAGGAUAUCACUUAAUUAGGCAUCAGAGGACCCACUCAGAAAAGACCUCCUAGCUAGGUCCCCAUGUGAGGAGAUCUGCUUUCAGCCCUCACCUAAGGGAGGUGAGGAAGAGGAAAAGCCCUCUUGUCAGCCUGGGAAGACCUUUUCGAGGGAGUCUCCCUGACCUGCUCAGAUCUGACAUUACCUCUUCCUGCAACUAAACACGAGCCUGGGCAGAACCUCUCAGCCUUCCUCUACGCCUUGAGGGGAUGUUUCAUCCAAAGUACAACCUGAAUUGAGGCUUCUCCUUCACUGGAGUGCACCUGCCUCUACCUCAUGGGUAUAAAGUAGGAGAACUAAGAGACUUAAGAGGUCGUGGUUCCUAUAUCGUCCAAAAAAUAGGCUGUUACAUAUCCUAAAGACUGCUCAACAGCUUCAAGUUGAAAGUGGCCAAGGACAGCCCCUUAGGUUUGGGAAGGGACGAGCCUGAAGGAUUCUGUCUUUACUGGGGUCAAAUCUUAAAGCACACAGCUCUGGACUCAAGACAGGAGGUUUGCGUCCUGAUGGCUUUGCCACACAUUCACAGGAUAACUGCAUAGAUCCCUCGCUGUCUGAUUCACUUCUUACCAUGCACUUUCCUUUGAUGCUGAGGAGAAAUGGAAGUGGGCGAAAAAUCUCAAGGCUGCUUCAUGUGGACCUUGUCAAGCUGCUCCCUCCCCCAGCGUCAAAUUGUUAUCAGGUGCCAAACACUGCUAGAAAGGAGGGCCUAGUCAGAAGCCUCUUUCCAUACGAGUUUUGGUUUUGUUUUUAAUAUUUUUUUCUAUUAAAAUACUCAUGCAUUUAACCUUCCCGUUAUUCAACCAGUCUCUUGGUUGCAUCCCUAGCACUUCUACUACAAGUGAGAUGGUAGUGUUUGAGUGCUUAUUGAGUAAAGCAUAAUUCGGUCAUAAUGAAAUCGUUCACAUUCCCUCAUAUGCACAAGCCCACCAACCCCUUCACACCCCCCUUCACAGGGGUCGUAUGAGUAAGGGGAUUUGGAAACUGUCAACUUACAAAGGCACUAUAACAAUUACAGAAUCAUGAUUGCCAUGGGCCACUUUAUUUACAUGAAGACAACUGGAGAACGACUAAGACCAAAUUAUGGAAAAUAAGAAAAAGCUGUUGCUGGCAAGACCAUCAAGACUGUUCUGACACCCUGUCCCCAUCAUCCCUGACUGAGUACUCUGACAUCACGGAAAGUGUUGAACCUGGGACCCUGAGGAAUUCACCAGGAGUAAAUGGCUUUCAUGUAUUUGUGUUGUUUGCUUUUUCUUACGUGAUUUUAUGUUCAUAGAGCUAGAAAGUAGCAUCUCAUGAUGGCCCAACAAUCUCUGUUGCCAGUUAAAGGUUCCUUGGAGAUGAGGCUGAAUAAUUAUGAACCUCACCUUCUCUGAUUGUGGGAGUGGCAAGAACUGGGGAGACGUCCUCCAUAAGUGGAGCACAGGGUAUGGGGUUAAAGCAUGACAGGGAGAGUCUUCUGUGCCUGGUUUCUUCUCCUCUAUCUCAUAAUGCAUUAUGGGCCCGAGGAAUAGGGGAGGGUUAAUAAGACUCCAACCCUAAUGGCCCAACAGGGAAAUUCUCAUUUUGGUCGAUGAUAUUCUGAUGGACUGGUUUGGUCUUAAUACCAGUCAACCGUUGUCCUUCUGGAAAUAUACAUAUAUGAAAUAAAUAAAGGUAACACUUGCAGCCAAGUUCCCUGGUUUCUGGGACUUCCCAUCUUACCCAUUCCUUUUCCAGGGCUUCAGUGUCCUGAUACUUCUGAGGGUGGUUCAUACUCAAAUAGAUCUGGGAGUACAGAGUAUUUUUCCUUGAGGAAAGGAAGGGUUGGGAUGAUUAGCAGAGUCCGGUGAAACAUAUGCACUCUGAGAUAAGAUCCAAGCCUGGAGUUUGCAGAAGAUACUGUCCUAAUAAGCAGGCAUUUCUAAACCAAGUAUCUAAGCCUAAGCACAGCUUGUCCUGGGUGAAAUGUCUGCCACAAAAGAUAGUUUCUCCUAGCUCAGACUUAACCAUUUAUAAAGGUUGGUAAAAUACUGGCAGUGACAACAAAUUGACUUUUUAAUUUUCUUAUUUGCAUUAUUCCAAUAAAUGAAAAUCUGUCAGAGUUCUACAUGAGGGAAA